GGUUCCGUUUCCGGCUGGCUGAGUACUGGGGUCCAGAAAGUGAUCGCUGCCGUGGUCGCCAUGGGGAAGUCGGAUUUUCUUACUCCCAAGGCUAUCGCCAACAGGAUCAAGUCCAAGGGGCUGCAGAAGCUACGCUGGUAUUGCCAGAUGUGCCAGAAGCAGUGCCGGGACGAGAAUGGCUUUAAGUGUCAUUGUAUGUCCGAAUCUCAUCAGAGACAACUAUUGCUGGCUUCAGAAAAUCCUCAGCAGUUUAUGGAUUAUUUUUCAGAGGAAUUCCGAAAUGACUUUCUAGAACUUCUCAGGAGACGCUUUGGCACUAAAAGGGUCCACAACAACAUUGUCUACAACGAAUACAUCAGCCACCGAGAGCACAUCCACAUGAAUGCCACUCAGUGGGAAACUCUGACUGAUUUUACUAAGUGGCUGGGCAGAGAAGGCUUGUGCAAAGUGGACGAGACACCAAAAGGCUGGUAUAUUCAGUACAUAGACAGGGACCCAGAAACUAUCCGCCGGCAACUGGAACUGGAGAAAAAGAAAAAGCAGGACCUUGAUGAUGAAGAAAAAACUGCCAAAUUUAUUGAAGAGCAAGUGAGAAGAGGCCUGGAAGGGAAGGAACAGGAGGUCCCUACUUUUACGGAAUUAAGCAGAGAAAAUGAUGAAGAGAAAGUCACGUUUAAUUUGAGUAAAGGAGCAUGUAGCUCAUCCGGAGCAACAUCUUCCAAGUCAAGUACUCUGGGACCGAGUGCACUGAAGACGAUAGGAAGUUCAGCAUCAGUGAAACGAAAAGAAUCUUCCCAGAGCUCAACUCAGUCUAAAGAAAAGAAGAAAAAGAAAUCUGCACUGGAUGAAAUCAUGGAGAUUGAAGAGGAAAAGAAAAGAACUGCCCGAACAGACUACUGGCUACAGCCUGAAAUUAUUGUGAAAAUUAUAACCAAGAAACUGGGAGAGAAAUAUCAUAAGAAAAAGGCUAUUGUUAAGGAAGUAAUUGACAAAUAUACAGCUGUUGUGAAGAUGAUUGAUUCUGGAGACAAGCUGAAACUUGACCAGACUCAUUUAGAGACAGUAAUUCCAGCACCAGGAAAAAGAAUUCUAGUUUUAAAUGGAGGCUACAGAGGAAAUGAAGGUACCCUAGAAUCCAUCAAUGAGAAGACUUUUUCAGCUACUAUCGUCAUUGAAACUGGCCCUUUAAAAGGACGCAGAGUUGAAGGAAUUCAAUAUGAAGACAUUUCUAAACUUGCCUGAGUUUGAAAAUUUGUUAACAAUACAUUAAAAUCUUAAAGCAUCAAAUUGGUGUUCGCCAAGGCAUUAUGAGACUCUACUGUGUUAGGGUAUAUUCUUUUGUAUAAAACAAACAGGUUUUUGAAAAUAUUACUGUAUAGUUGUUCAGCUAAACUUUGAGAAGAAUUUAAUUAUGUCUCAUGAGGUAUCAAACUAUGUAAUUUUGUCCUUGUUAUUUUUGUUUCCUUUGUAAUUUACUUGAUGAGUUUAUAUCUUCAUUAAAGAAUGUUAUUAUAAAGUGUUUUAUCUAUGACAAUUUAGAAUCAUGUAAUUGGAGGAAAUCCUUCAUACACUCUAUAUUUUCAGUAGUAGAGUAGUAAAGUUGAACUCUAAGUGUGACUAAAUUUUAAAUGUCAAACUAUAAAUAUAGAAGCAGCUUUAUUGUGGUAAUAAUUCAUAUACCAUACAGUUCACUCAUUUAAAAUAUACAUACAAUUCAGUGGUUUUUAGUAUUUUUGCAGAAUUGUGCAGCCAUCACCACUGUCUGAUUUUAAAACACUUUCAUACCCCAAAAUGAAACCCUUUAAUAGUCAAUCGCUAUUUUUCCCCUCUGCCCUAGCCCUAGACAGCCACUAAUGUACUUUCUGUCUCUAUGGAUUUGCCCUUUCUGGACAUUUCUUAUAAAUGGAAUCAUAUAAUAUGUGAUCUUUUAUGACUGGCUUCUUACACUUAGCAUCAUGUUUUCAAGGUUUAUCCAUGCAGUAGCAUGUAGGCGUGCUUCAUUUGUUUUUAUGGCUGCUUAAUAUUCCACUGUAUGGAUGUACCGUAUUUUGUUUGUCCAUUCAUCAGCUGAUAAACAUUUAGAUUGUUUCUACUUUUUGGCUAUUGUGAAUAAUGCUGCCAUGAUCACCCAUUUACAGGAUUUUAUGUGAACAGAAGCUUUCGCUUCUGCCAAACUCUUCCAGAGCAGCUAUACCAUUUUACAGUCCUACCAGCAAUGUUGAACUAUAGUUUUAUUUGUUUUUAAUUUUUUUACUUUUAGAGACAUGGUCUCACUGUGUUGCCCAGGCUGCUGUCAAACUCCUGGGCUCAAGUGAUCCUCCUGCCUCAGCCUCCCAAAGUGCUAGGAUUGCAGGUGUGAGCCACAGCACCCUGCCUAACCAUACAGUUUGAAAUAAGUAGGGCAGUGUAUUAUUAGGGAAUGCAAAAGACAGGAAACCCACAUUUGCCUGUGCCAAAGGAAAAACGAAGGGAUAUUUGUAGUGCACAUGACUGAAAGGAGCAGACGCUAGCUUCCAGGGCAGCGGGACCGGGUGUGAACAGCCUUCCCUGGGCUUCCGCUCUGUCUCUGGCUCCUGUGCUGGCUCUCUACAUUUACAUUCUUGAGCACUCUAGGUUUACAUCUUACCCUUCAGCAGCACCGGGAAGAGAGAGAUGAUCUAUCUUUUCUUUUUCUUUUUUUUUUUUUUUCUGACACAGAGUCUCACUCUGUCACCCAGGCUGAUUGCAGUAGUGCAAUCUCGGCUCACUGCAACCUCCACCUCCCGGGUUCAAGCCAUUCUCCUGCCUCAGCCUCCUGAGUAGCUGGGACUACAGGCAUGCGCCACCACGCCCAGCUAAUUUUUGUAAUUUUAGAAGAGAUGAGGUUUCACCAUGUUGGCCAGGAUGGUCUCGAUCUCUUGACCUUAUGAUCUGCCCGCCUCAGCCUCCCAAAGUGCUGGGAUUACAGGCAUGAGCCACUACGCCUCUUUUUUUUUGUUCUGUUUUUUGAGAUAGGGUCUUGCUCUGUCAUCCAGCCUGGAGUGCAGUGGCACAAUCAUGGCUCACUGCAGCCUCGUCCUCCUGGGCUUAGGUCAUUGAUUCUCCCACCUCAGCCUCCCGAGUAGCUGGGACUACAGGCAUGCACUACCAUGCCUGGCUAAUUUUUUUGAUUUUUAGUAGAGAUGAGGUCUUGCUAUGUUGCCCAGGCUGGUCUCAAACUCUUGAGCUCAAGCAAUCCUCCUGCCUCGGCCUUCUAAAAUGUUGUGAUUACAGGUGUGAGCUACCACGCCUUGCCUGAGUUGAUCUUCUACAAGAGUUCAAACAAAAAACAGACCAUACCAGGAUGAUCACUUCAAACAUGAGGAUGGGUAUAAGCUGACGUCAGACACAGGUAUGGUGCCAAACCCUGGGAUCUCUCUCUUUAACUGAGAGUCAGGGAGGGCUGAUUGCUUCUAUUCUCAGAAGAUGGGAGAACGUAUGCUGUUAGCAGAAAUGUAAGAGGCAGUAAAGAAAUACUAAUAGGAUGAUGGCAGAAGCUUUACAGAAAAUGUUCCUCAGGGAUGAAUUAAGGUUUUUCCAAAGUAACCUGACAGCACAUUAUGGAAAGCAACUGGGUUUUGGGUGUGGGCAGUCUUUAGAUCAAAUUCUGGCAGUUCUGUUCAUUGGCUUUGUAAUAUUAGAAUGUUAAUGUUCUUGAAUUGCAAUGUUUUUAAUGUAUAAAUUGUCAAAAUGUUUUUCAGCAGGGUUGAUGGGAGACCUACAGAAAAUACAUAUAAAUCAUCAGACAUGAAGUCCAGCACAUAGUAGGUAUUGAAUAAAUGGCAGUGAGUGGUCAUGUCCAGAAAUGAAGCCAAGAAGUUGAGCCUGGACUACUAAGAAUCUGGUCUGAAGAAUUUCAAAAAGGAGAAUGGUUCUCCCUGAUAACAAAUAGUGAUGAGUAAAACCAGACAAAUUACAUAUGCCUCCCCCAAGUAUGUACGUUUGGAAUCAACUUGGUGGUUUUCUUCAGAGAAAAAAUGUUUCAUGUCUGCCUCCCACAUUUAAUUCUCCAACGUCUUUCUGAAAUUAUUUCAGAAUGAAAUGAGGCAGCAUACUUGAGGUUAAAUUCAAUAAAAAAUAUCUGAAGCAUAAAAAUACGAUUAUAGACUUCACAGUAGUUUUUUCCCUCUGAGUCUGUAGAACUUGAUAGAGUUUAUGCUAAGCAAAAUGACUGCAGAUAACUAACAACAGGUCUCAUAUUAGACUUUGAUUUUUGAAGUAUCAUAAGCUAUUUUUCUUUAUUUCAAACAUAGACUUUACUUUUUAGAGCAGUCUCUGUGGGUUUUGACAAAUGUAUAAUGACAUGCAUCUGCCACUGUAGUAUCACACAGAACAGUUUCACUGCCCUAGAAGUUUCCUGUGUUCUGUCUGUUCCCUGUCUCCCCCCAAAUCCCUGCUGACCGCUGAUCUUUUUACUGUCUCCCUAGUUUUGUCUCCAUCGAAGGUCAUAUAGUUGGAGUCACACAGGGUGUAGCUUUUUCAGAUUGGCUUCUUUCACCUGGUAGAACAUAUGCAUGUAAGGUUCCUCCAUGUUGUUUUGGUUAGGUUUUUGUGGCUCGAUAGCGCACUUCAUUUUAGCACUGCAUAUUCUAUUGUCUGAAUGCACCACAGUUUAUGCACUCACCUACUGAAGGAUAUCUUGGUUGCUUACAAGGUUUGGAAAUUAUGAGUAAAGCUGCUACAAACAUCUGUGCGCAGGUUUUUUGUGGAUAGACGUUUUCAACUUAUUUACGUAACGACCAAAGAGCACAAUUGCUGGAUCAUAUGCCAGGAGUCUUCUGAGAAACUACCAACCUGUCUUCCAGAGUGACUGUACCAUUUUGUAUUCAAACGAGCAGUGAAUGAGAGUUCCUGCUGCUCUGCAUCUCCGUCAGCAUUUGAUGUUGUCAGUGUUCUGGAUUUUGGCCAUCUUAAUAGCUGUACAGUGGGAUCUUGUCAUUGCUUUAAUUUGCAUUUCUUUGAUGAAGUAUGAUGUGGAGCAUCUUUUCAUGGGCUUAUUUGCCACCUGUAUAUCUUCUCUGGUGAGAUGUCUUUCAGGUUUUUUGCCCAUUAUUUAAUUGGGUUACUCAUUUUCUUAUUGUUGAAUUUUAAGAGUUGUUUGUAUAUUUCAGUUGUGUUCUUUAUCGAAUGUGUCUUUUGCAAGUAUUUUCUCUCAGUCAGUGGCCUGUCUUCUCAUUUUGUUUUAAGCUAUUCUUUUUUAACACCCCAAGAUUUUCAUCGUUACUUUUUUUUUUUUUUUUUUUUUUUUUUUUUUUUUUUUUUGAGACGGAGUCUCGCUCUGUCGCCCAGGCCGGACUGCGGACUGCAGUGGCGCAAUCUCGGCUCACUGCAAGCUCCGCUUCCCGGGUUCACGCCAUUCUCCUGCCUCAGCCUCCCGAGUAGCUGGGACUACAGGCGCCCGCCACCGCGCCCGGCUAAUUUUUUGUAUUUUUAGUACAUCGUUACUUUUAAGACCACUGUGCACACAUAAAAUACUAAAAGCUAAACUUAAUAUCUGCAGGUAGAAGUUUUAAAUUCAAGAUUUUAACCAAAUAACAGAGUUAAUGCUAAAAUCUCACUUUUGAAGUUUAUGUUGAAUAUUAGCAUUCUAAUAUUUAAUAUUUUUCUAUUUUUGAAAUAGGAAAUGGAAAAGAUGCAGUAGGUUUUUCAAAAGGGUAUCAUAGGUGAGCACUUCUUAUAGAAGAAGAAAACUAAGAGGUAGUGCUAUUUACCUCUUCAGCACUAAGUUUAUCUUUAUUUUUAUUUAUUUCUAUAAAGAGAUGGGAGUCUCACUGUGUUGCUUAGGCUGGUCUUGAACUCCUGGCCUCCAGUGAUGCUCCUGCCUUGGCCUCCGAGAGUGCUGGGAUUAUAGGCAUGAGGCACCACACCCAGCCAGUAAUCUUUAGCUUCUAGAAACAAUCAGAUUUCCUUAAGAUUUUGCAAUUAGGUUUAGAGGAGCUCACUUGCUUUUUCAAAUAUGGGUUGGAUAUGUCCAAAAAAAGAGUUUUGCCUCUACAAUGAAAAAUGAUUUUUACCAGAUUAUGGAAAGGAAGAUUCAUAAAAAUGUGCCUUUAAAAAGCUUUUUUAAAGUGCAAGUUCACCAAUUUGACUUUUGAAAAUACGUUCAUUUUAGGAAUUGAUUUUUUAAGGAAAGUUGUAAACACAGCAAAGCACAGAAUUACACUGGUUCAGACUUGCAUCUUAGCACCAAAAUCCACUAUACAAAUGCAGACAGCAUAAAGUAACCUAGUUUCGCUUUAAAUUUGUUGCUUAUUUUAUUCUCCCUUAUAAAUGUCAUUGGUCUUUUGUUAGAACAUAAUUUACUACUUUAUUUUGAAAUAAAGUCUAAGAUUUAGCAUGUAA